CUCCUGCUUCCUAUUUUGGUUCAUCCAGGAACCACAGAGGACACAUUAAUAACUGGAAGUAAAACUGCUGCCCCAGUCACCUCAACAGGCUCAACAACAGCGACACUAGAGGGACAAUCAACUGCAGCUUCUUCAAGGACCUCUAAUCAGGACAUAUCAGCUUCAUCUCAGAACCACCAGACUAAGAGCACGGAGACCACCAGCAAAGCUCAAACCGACACCCUCACGCAGAUGAUGACAUCAACUCUUUUUUCUUCCCCAAGUGUACACAAUGUGAUGGAGACAGCUCCUCCAGAUGAAAUGACCACAUCAUUUCCCUCCAGUGUCACCAACACACUCAUGAUGACAUCAAAGACUAUAACAAUGACAACCUCCACAGACUCCACUCUUGGAAACACAGAAGAGACAUCAACAGCAGGAACUGAAAGUUCUACCCCAGUGACCUCAGCAGUCUCAAUAACAGCUGGACAGGAAGGACAAUCACGAACAACUUCCUGGAGGACCUCUAUCCAAGACACAUCAGCUUCUUCUCAGAACCACUGGACUCGGAGCACGCAGACCACCAGGGAAUCUCAAACCAGCACCCUAACACACAGAACCACUUCAACUCCUUCUUUCUCUCCAAGUGUACACAAUGUGACAGGGACUGUUUCUCAGAAGACAUCUCCUUCAGGUGAAACAGCUACCUCAUCCCUCUGUAGUGUCACAAACACAUCCAUGAUGACAUCAGAGAAGAUAACAGUGACAACCUCCACAGGCUCCACUCUUGGAAACCCAGGGGAGACAUCAUCAGUACCUGUUACUGGAAGUCUUAUGCCAGUCACCUCAGCAGCCUUAGUAACAUUUGAUCCAGAAGGACAAUCACCAGCAACUUUCUCAAGGACUUCUACUCAGGACACAACAGCUUUUUCUAAGAACCACCAGACUCAGAGCGUGGAGACCACCAGAGUAUCUCAAAUCAACACCCUCAACACCCUCACACCGGUUACAACAUCAACUGUUUUAUCCUCACCAAGUGGAUUCAACCCAAGUGGAACAGUUUCUCAGGAGACAUUCCCUUCUGGUGAAACAACCACCUCAUCCCCUUCCAGUGUCAGCAAUACAUUCCUGGUAACAUCAAAGGUGUUCAGAAUGCCAACCUCCAGAGACUCUACUCUUGGAAACACAGAGGAGACAUCACUAUCUGUAAGUGGAACCAUUUCUGCAAUCACUUCCAAAGUUUCAACCAUAUGGUGGUCAGACACUCUGUCAACAGCACUCUCCCCCAGUUCUCUACCUCCAAAAAUAUCCACAGCUUUCCACACCCAGCAGAGUGAAGGUGCAGAGACCACAGGACGGCCUCAUGAGAGGAGCUCAUUCUCUCCAGGUGUGUCUCAAGAAAUAUUUACUCUACAUGAAACAACAACAUGGCCUUCCUCAUUCUCCAGCAAAGGCCACACAACUUGGUCACAAACAGAACUGCCCUCAACAUCAACAGGUGCUGCCACUAGGCUUGUCACAGGAAAUCCAUCUACAGGGACAGCUGGCACUAUUCCAAGGGUCCCCUCUAAGGUCUCAGCAAUAGGGGAACCAGGAGAGCCCACCACAUACUCCUCCCACAGCACAACUCUCCCAAAAACAACAGGGGCAGGCGCCCAGACACAAUGGACACAAGAAACGGGGACCACUGGAGAGGCUCUUCUCAGCAGCCCAAGCUACAGUGUGACUCAGAUGAUAAAAACGGCCACAUCCCCAUCUUCUUCACCUAUGCUGGAUAGACACACAUCCCAACAAAUUACAACGGCACCAUCAACAAAUCAUUCAACAAUACAUUCCACAAGCACCUCUCCUCAGGAAUCACCAGCUGUUUCCCAAAGGGGUCACACUCAAGCCCCGCAGACCACACAAGAAUCACAAACCACGAGGUCCGUCUCCCCCAUGACUGACACCAAGACAGUCACCACCCCAGGUUCUUCCUUCACAGCCAGUGGGCACUCGCCCUCAGAAAUUGUUCCUCAGGACGCACCCACCAUAAGUGCAGCAACAACCUUUGCCCCAGCUCCCACCGGGGAUGGUCACACAACCCAGGCCCCGACCACAGCACUGCAGGCAGCACCCAGCAGCCAUGAUGCCACCCUGGGGCCCUCAGGAGGCACGUCACUUUCCAAAACAGGUGCCCUUACUCUGGCCAACUCUGUAGUGUCAACACCAGGGGGCCCAGAAGGACAAUGGACAUCAGCCUCUGCCAGCACCUCACCUGACACAGCAGCAGCCAUGACCCAUACCCACCAGGCUGAGAGCACAGAGGCCUCUGGACAAACACAGACCAGCGAACCGGCCUCCUCAGGGUCACGAACCACCUCAGCGGGCACAGCUACCCCUUCCUCAUCCGGGGCGAGUGGCACAACACCUUCAGGAAGCGAAGGAAUAUCCACCUCAGGAGAGACGACAAGGUUUUCAUCAAACCCCUCCAGGGACAGUCACACAACCCAGUCAACAACCGAAUUGCUGUCCGCCUCAGCCAGUCAUGGUGCCAUCCCAGUAAGCACAGGAAUGGCGUCUUCGAUCGUCCCCGGCACCUUUCAUCCCACCCUCUCUGAGGCCUCCACUGCAGGGAGACCGACAGGACAGUCAAGCCCAACUUCUCCCAGUGCCUCUCCUCAGGAGACAGCCGCCAUUUCCCGGAUGGCCCAGACUCAGAGGACAAGAACCAGCAGAGGGUCUGACACUAUCAGCCUGGCGUCCCAGGCAACCGACACCUUCUCAACAGUCCCACCCACACCUCCAUCGAUCACAUCCACUGGGCUUACAUCUCCACAAACCGAGACCCACACUCUGUCACCUUCAGGGUCUGGUAAAACCUUCACCACGGCCCUCAUCAGCAACGCCACCCCUCUUCCUGUCACCUACGCUUCCUCGGCAUCCACAGGUCACACCACCCCUCUUCAUGUCACCGAUGCUUCCUCAGUAUCCACAGGUCACGCCACCCCUCUUCCUGUCACCAGCCCUUCCUCAGUAUCCACAGGUCACACCACCCCUCUUCCUGUCACCGACACUUCCUCAGAAUCCACAGGUCACGUCACCCCUCUUCCUGUCACCAGCUUUUCCUCAGCAUCCACAGGUGACAGCACCCCUCUUCCUGUCACUGACACUUCCUCAGCAUCCACAGGUCACGUCACCCCUCUUCCUGUCACCAGCCUUUCCUCAGCAUCCACAGGUGACACCACCCCUCUUCCUGUCACUGACACUUCCUCAGCAUCCACAGGUCACGCCACCUCUCUUCCUGUCACCGACACUUCCUCAGUAUCCACAGGUCACACCACCCCUCUUCCUGUCACCGACACUUCCUCAGCAUCCACAGGUCACGCCACCUCUCUUCCUGUCACCGACACUUCCUCAGUAUCCACAGGUCACACCACCCCUCUUCAUGUCACUGAUGCUUCCUCAGCAUCCACAGGUCAGGCCACCCCUCUUCCUGUCACCAGCCUUUCCUCAGUAUCCACAGGUGACACCACGCCUCUUCCUGUCACUAGCCCUUCCUCAGCAUCCACAGGUCACGCCACCCCUCUUCUUGUCACCGACACUUCCUCAGCAUCCACAGGACACGCCACCCCUCUUCCUGUCACCGACGCUUCCUCAGUGUCCACAGAUCACGCCACCUCUCUUCCUGUAACCAUCCCUUCCGCAGCAUCCACAGGUCACACCACCCCUCUUCCUGUCACCGACACUUCCUCAGCAUCCACAGGUCAGGCCACCUCUCUUCUUGUCACCGACACUUCCUCAGUAUCCACAGGUGACACCACGCCUCUUCCUGUCACUAGCACUUCCUCAGCAUCCACAGGUCACGUCACUCCUCUUCAUGUCACCAGCCCUUCCUCAGCAUCCACAGGUCACGCCACCCCUCUUCCUGUCACCAGCCUUUCCUCAGCAUCCACAGGUGACACCAUGCCUCUUCCUGUCACUAGCCCUUCCUCAGCAUCCACAGGUGACACCACCCCUCUUCCUGUCACCGACGCUUCCUCAGUAUCCACAGGUCACACCACCCCUCUUCAUGUCACUGAUGCUUCCUCAGCAUCCACAGGUCAGGCCACCCCUCUUCCUGUCACCAGCCUUUCCUCAGUAUCCACAGGUGACACCACGCCUCUUCCUGUCACUAGCCCUUCCUCAGCAUCCACAGGUCACGCCACCCCUCUUCUUGUCACCGACACUUCCUCAGCAUCCACAGGACACGCCACCCCUCUUCCUGUCACCGACGCUUCCUCAGUGUCCACAGAUCACGCCACCUCUCUUCCUGUAACCAUCCCUUCCGCAGCAUCCACAGGUCACACCACCCCUCUUCCUGUCACCGACACUUCCUCAGCAUCCACAGGUCAGGCCACCUCUCUUCUUGUCACCGACACUUCCUCAGUAUCCACAGGUGACACCACGCCUCUUCCUGUCACUAGCACUUCCUCAGCAUCCACAGGUCACGUCACUCCUCUUCAUGUCACCAGCCCUUCCUCAGCAUCCACAGGUCACGCCACCCCUCUUCCUGUCACCAGCCUUUCCUCAGCAUCCACAGGUGACACCAUGCCUCUUCCUGUCACUAGCCCUUCCUCAGCAUCCACAGGUGACACCACCCCUCUUCCUGUCACCGACGCUUCCUCAGUAUCCACAGGUCACACCACCCCUCUUCCUGUCACCAGCCCUUCCUCAGCAUCUACAGGUCACACCACCCCUCUUCCUGUCACCGACACUUCCUCAGCAUCCAAAGGUGACACCACCCCUCUUCCUGUCACCAGCCCUUCCUCAGCAUCUACAGGUCACACCACCCCUCUUCCUGUCACCGACACUUCCUCAGCAUCCACAGGUGACACCACCCCUCUUCCUGUCACCAAUGCUUCCUCAUUAUCCACAGGUCACGCCACCCCUCUUCAUGUCACCAGCCCUUCCUCAGCAUCCACAGGUCACGCCACCCCUCUUCCUGUCACCAGCACUUCCUCAGCAUCCACCGGUCACGCCACCCCUCUUCCUGUCACCGGCCUUUCCUCAGCUACCACAGAUGACACCACCCGUCUUCCUGUCACCGACGUUUCCUCGGCAUCCACAGGUCAGGCCACCCCUCUUCCUGUCACCAGCCUUUCCUCAGUAUCCACAGGUGACACCACGCCUCUUCCUGUCACUAGCCCUUCCUCAGCAUCCACAGGUCACGCCAGCCCUCUUCUUGUCACUGACGCUUCCUCAGCAUCCACAGGUCAGGCCACCCCUCUUCCUGUCACCGACACUUCCUCAGUAUCCACAGCUCACGCCACCCCACUUCCUGUCACCGGCCUUUCUUCAGCUUCCACAGAUGACACCACCCGUCUUCCUGUCACCGACGUUUCCUCGGCAUCCACAGGUCAGGCCAUCCCUCUUCCUGUCACCAGCCCUUCCUCAGCAUCCACAGGUGACACCACCCCUCUUCCUGUCACCGACGCUUCCUCAGCAUCCACAGGUGACACCACCUCUCUUCCUGUCACCAUCCCUUCCUCAGCAUCUUCAGGUCACACCACCUCUCUUCCUGUCACCGACGCUUCCUCAGUGUCCACAGGUCACGCCACCUCUCUUCUUGUCACCGACGCUUCCUCAGUAUCCACAGGUGACACCACCCCUCUUCCUGUCACCGACACUAACUCAGCAUCCACAGGUGACACCACCCCUCUUCAUGUCACCGACGCUUCCUCAGUAUCCACAGGUCACGCCACCUCUCUUCCUGUCACCAGCCUUUCCUCAGCAUCCACAGGUGACACCACGCCUCUUCCUGUCACUAGCCCUUCCUCAGCAUCCUCAGGUCACACCACCCCUCUUCCUGUCACCGACGCUUCCUCAGUACCCACAGGUCACGCCACCUCUCUUCCUGUCACCGACGCUUCCUCAGUGUCCACAGGUCACGCCACCCCUCUUCCUGUCACCGACGCUUCCUCAGUGUCCACAGGUCAUGCCACCCCUCUUCCGGUCACCGACACUUCCUCAGUAUCUACAGGACAGGCCACCCCUCUUCCUGUCACCAGCCUUUCCUCAGCAUCCACAGGUGACACCACCCCUCUUCCUGUCACCGACACUUCCUCAGCAUCCACAGGUCACGCCCCCCAUCUUCCUGUCACCGGCCUUUCCUCAGCUUCCACAGGUGACACCACCCGUCUUCCUGUCACCAACGUUUCCUCGGCAUCCACAGGUCAUGCCACCCCUCUUCCUGUCACCAGCACUUCCUCAGCAUCCACAGGUGACACCACCCCUCUUCCUGGCACCGACACUUCCUCAGUAUCCACAGGUCACACCACCCCUCUUCUUGUCACCGACGCUUCGUCAGUAUCCACAGGUGACACCACCCGUCUUCCUGUCACCAGCCCUUCCUCAGCAUCUACAGGUCACACCACCCCUCUUCAUGUCACCGAUGCUUCCUCAGUAUCCACAGGUCACACCACCCCUCUUCCUGUCACCGACACUUCCUCAGCAUCCACAGGUCAGGCCACCUCUCUUCUUGUCACCGACACUUCCUCAGUAUCCACAGGUGACACCACGCCUCUUCCUGUCACUAGCACUUCCUCAGCAUCCACAGGUCACGUCACUCCUCUUCAUGUCACCAGCCCUUCCUCAGCAUCCACAGGUCACGCCACCCCUCUUCCUGUCACCAGCCUUUCCUCAGCAUCCACAGGUGACACCACCCCUCUUCCUGUCACCGACACUUCCUCAGUAUCCACAGGUCACACCACCCCUCUUCCUGUCACCAGCCCUUCCUCAGCAUCUACAGGUCACACCACCCCUCUUCCUGUCACCGACACUUCCUCAGCAUCCAAAGGUGACACCACCCCUCUUCCUGUCACCAGCCCUUCCUCAGCAUCUACAGGUCACACCACCCCUCUUCCUGUCACCGACACUUCCUCAGCAUCCACAGGUGACACCACCCCUCUUCCUGUCACCAAUGCUUCCUCAUUAUCCACAGGUCACGCCACCCCUCUUCAUGUCACCAGCCCUUCCUCAGCAUCCACAGGUCACGCCACCCCUCUUCCUGUCACCAGCACUUCCUCAGCAUCCACCGGUCACGCCACCCCUCUUCCUGUCACCAGCACUUCCUCAGCAUCCACCGGUCACGCCACCCCUCUUCCUGUCACCGACAAUUCCUCAGUAUCCACAGGUCAUGCCACCCCUCUUCCUGUCACCGGCCUUUCCUCAGCUACCACAGAUGACACCACCCGUCUUCCUGUCACCGACGUGUCCUCGGCAUCCACAGGUCAGGCCACCCCUCUUCCUGUCACCAGCCUUUCCUCAGUAUCCACAGGUGACACCACGCCUCUUCCUGUCACUAGCCCUUCCUCAGCAUCCACAGGUCACGCCAGCCCUCUUCUUGUCACUGACGCUUCCUCAGCAUCCACAGGUCAGGCCACCCCUCUUCCUGUCACCGACACUUCCUCAGUAUCCACAGCUCACGCCACCCCACUUCCUGUCACCGGCCUUUCCUCAGCUUCCACAGAUGACACCACCCGUCUUCCUGUCACCGACGUUUCCUCGGCAUCCACAGGUCAGGCCAUCCCUCUUCCUGUCACCAGCCCUUCCUCAGCAUCCACAGGUGACACCACCCCUCUUCCUGUCACCGACGCUUCCUCAGCAUCCACAGGUGACACCACCUCUCUUCCUGUCACCAUCCCUUCCUCAGCAUCUUCAGGUCACACCACCUCUCUUCCUGUCACCGACGCUUCCUCAGUGUCCACAGGUCACGCCACCUCUCUUCUUGUCACCGACGCUUCCUCAGUAUCCACAGGUGACACCACCCCUCUUCCUGUCACCGACACUAACUCAGCAUCCACAGGUGACACCACCCCUCUUCAUGUCACCGACGCUUCCUCAGUAUCCACAGGUCACGCCACCUCUCUUCCUGUCACCAGCCUUUCCUCAGCAUCCACAGGUGACACCACGCCUCUUCCUGUCACUAGCCCUUCCUCAGCAUCCUCAGGUCACACCACCUCUCUUCCUGUCACCGACGCUUCCUCAGUGUCCACAGGUCACGCCACCUCUCUUCCUGUCACCAUCCCUUCCUCAGCAUCCUCAGGUCACACCACCCCUCUUCCUGUCACCGACGCUUCCUCAGUACCCACAGGUCACGCCACCUCUCUUCCUGUCACCGACGCUUCCUCAGUGUCCACAGGUCACGCCACCCCUCUUCCUGUCACCGACGCUUCCUCAGUGUCCACAGGUCAUGCCACCCCUCUUCCGGUCACCGACACUUCCUCAGUAUCUACAGGACAGGCCACCCCUCUUCCUGUCACCAGCCCUUCCUCAGCAUCCACAGGUCACGCCACCCAUCUUCUUGUCACCGACGCUUCCUCAGUAUCCACAGGUCACGCCACCUCUCUUCUUGUCACCGACGCUUCCUCAGUAUCCACAGGUCACGCCACCCCUCUUCCUGUCACCAGCCCUUCCUCAGCAUCCACAGGUGACACCACCCCUCUUCCUGUCACCGACACUUCCUCAGUAUCCACAGGUCACGCCACCUCUCUUCCUGUCACUGACACUUCCUCAGCAUCCACAGGUCACGCCACCUCUCUUCCUGUCACCGACACUUCCUCAGCAUCCACAGGUCAGGCCACCCCUCUUCCUGUCACCAGCCCUUCCUCAGCAUCCACAGGUCACGCCAUCCCUCUUCUUGUCACCGACACUUCCUCAGCAUCCACAGGACAGGCCACCCCUCUUCCUGUCACCAGCCUUUCCUCAGCAUCCACAGGUGACACCACCCCUCUUCCUGUCACCGAUGCUUCCUCAGUGUCCACAGGUCACGCCACCUCUCUUCCUGUCACCAGCCUUUCCUCAGUAUCCACAGGUGACACCACCCCUCUUCCUGUCACUAGCCCUUCCUCAGCAUCCACAGGUCACGCCACCCCUCUUCAUGUCACCAGCCCUUCCUCAGCAUCCACAGGUCACGCCACCCCUCUUCCUGUCACCAGCCUUUCCUCAGCAUCCACAGGUGACACCACGCCUCUUCCUGUCACUAGCCCUUCCUCAGCAUCCACAGGUCACGCCACCCCUCUUCAUGUCACCGACGCUUCCUCAGUAUCCACAGGUGACACCACCCCUCUUCCUGUCACCAGCCCUUCCUCAGCAUCCUCAGGUCACACCACCCCUCUUCCUGUCACCGACGCUUCCUCAGCAUCCACAGGUGACACCACCCCUCUUCCUGUCACCGACACUUCCUCAGCAUCCACAGGUCACGCCACCCAUCUUCCUGUCACCGGCCUUUCCUCAGCUUCCACAGGUGACACCACCCGUCUUCCUGUCACCGACGUUUCCUCGGCAUCCACAGGUCAUGCCACCCCUCUUCCUGUCACCAGCACUUCCUCAGCAUCCACAGGUGACACCACCCCUCUUCCUGGCACCGACACUUCCUCAGUAUCCACAGGUCACACCACCCCUCUUCUUGUCACCGACGCUUCGUCAGUAUCCACAGGUGACACCACCCGUCUUCCUGUCACCAGCCCUUCCUCAGCAUCUACAGGUCACACCACCCCUCUACCUGUCACCGACACUCCCUCAGCAUCCACAGGUGACACCACCCCUCUUCCUGUCACCAAUGCUUCCUCAUUAUCCACACGUCACGCCACCUCUCUUCAUGUCACCAGCCCUUCCUCAGCAUCCACCGGUCACGCCACCCCUCUUCCUGUUACCGACACUUCCGCAGCAUCCACAGGUCACGCCACCCCUCUUCCUGUCACCAGCACUUCCUCAGCAUCCACAGGUGACACCACCCCUCUUCCUGUCACCGACACUUCCUCAGCAUCCACAGGUCAUGCCACCCCUCUUCCUGUCACCAACACUUCCUCAGUAUCCACAGGUCACGCCACCCCUCUUCAUGUCACCAGCCCUUCCUCAGCAUCCACAGGUCACACCACCCCUCUUCCUGUCACCGACGCUUCGUCAGUGUCCACAGGUCACGCCACCUCUCUUCCUGUCACCGACGCUUCCUCAGUGUCCACAGGUCACGCCACCCCUCUUCCUGUCACCGACGCUUCCUCAGUGUCCACAGGUCACGCUACCCCUCUUCCUCUCACCAGCCUUUCCUCAGUAUCCACAGGUGACACCACGCCUCUUCCUGUCACCGACACUUCCUCAGCAUCCACAGGUCAGGCCACCCCUCUUCCUGUCACCAGCCUUUCCUCAGUAUCCACAGGUGACACCACCCCUCUUCCUGUCACCGACACUUCCUCAGCAUCCACAGGUCACGCCACCUCUCUUCCUGUCACCGACACUUCCUCAGCAUCCACAGGUCACGCCACCCCUCUUCAUGUCACCAGCCCUUCCUCAGCAUCCACCGGUCACGCCACCCCGCUUCCUGUCACCGACACUUCCUCAGCAUCCACAGGUCACGCCACCCCUCUUCCUGUCACCAGCCUUUCCUCAGUAUCCACAGGUGACACCACGCCUCUUCCUGUCACUAGCCCUUCCUCAGCAUCCACAGGUCACGCCACUCCUCUUCUUGUCACCGACGCUUCCUCAGCAUCCACAGGUCAGGCCACCCCUCUUCCUGUCACCAGCCUUUCCUCAGUAUCCACAGGUGACACCACGCCUCUUCCUGUCACUAGCCCUUCCUCAGCAUCCACCGGUCAUGCCACCUCUCUUCCUGUCACCGACACUUCCUCAGCAUCCACAGGUGACACCACCUCUCUUCCUGUCACCGACACUUCCUCAGCAUACACAGGUGACACCACCUCUCUUCCUGUCACCGACACUUCCUCAUCAUCCACAGGUGACACCACCCCUCUUCUUGUCACCGAGACUUCCUCAGCAUCCACAGGUGACACCACCCCUGUGCCUGUCACCGACACUUCCUCAGUAUCCACAGGUCACGCCACCCCUCUUCCUGUCACCGGCCUUUCCUCAGCUUCCACAGGUGACACCACCCGUCUUCCUGUCACCGACAUUUCCUCGGCAUCCACAGGUCAGGCCACCCCUCUUCCUGUCACCAACACUUCCUCAGUAUCCACAGGUGACACCAUGCCUCUUCCUGUCACUAGCCCUUCCUCAGCAUCCACAGGUCACGCCACCCCUCUUCCUGUCACCAGCACUUCCUCAGCAUCCACCGGUCACGCCACCCCUGUUCCUGUCACCAGCACUUCCUCAGCAUCCACAGGUCACACCACCCCUCUUCCUGUCACCAGCCCUUCCUCAGCAUCUACAGGUCACACCACCCCUCUUCCUGUCACCGACACUUCCUCAGCAUCCACAGGUGACACCACCCCUCUUCCUGUCACCAAUGCUUCCUCAUUAUCCACAGGACACACCACCCCUCUUCAUGUCACCAUCCCUUCCUCAGCAUCCACAGGUGACACCAGCACUCUUCCUGUCACCGGCGCUUCCUCAGCAUCCACCGGUCACGCCACCCCUCUUCCUGUCACCGACACUUCCUCAGUAUCCACAGGUCACGCCACCCCUCUUCCUGUCACCAGCUUUUCCUCAGUAUCCACAGGUGACACCACCCCUCUUCCUGUCACCGACGCUUCCUCGGCAUCCACCGGUCACGCCACCCCUCUUCCUGUCACCGACACUUCCUCAGCAUCCACAGGUGACACCACCCCUCUUCCUGUCACCGACGCUUCCUCGGCAUCCACAGGUCAGGCCACCCCUCUUCCUGUCACCAGCCUUUCCUCAGUAUCAACAGGUGACACCACGCCUCUUCCUGUCACCAUCCCUUCCUCAGCAUCCUCAGGUCACACCACCUCUCUUCCUGUCAGCGACACUUCCUCAGCAUCCACAGGUCAGGCCACCCCUCUUCCUGUCACCAGCCUUUCCUCAGUAUCCACAGGUGACACCACCCCUCUUCUUGUCACCGACGCUUCCUCAGUAUCCACAGGUCACGCCACCCCUCUUCCUGUCACCGACACUUCCUCAGCAUCCACAGGUGACACCACCCGUCUUCCUGUCACGGACACUUCCUCAGCAUCCACAGGUCAGGCCACCCCUCUUCCUGUCACCAGCCUUUCCUCAGUAUCCACAGGUGACACCACCCCUCUUCUUGUCACCAACACUUCCUCAGUAUCCACAGGUCACGCCACCUCUCUUCCUGUCACCAUCCCUUCCUCAUCAUCCUCAGGUCACACCACCCCUCUUCCUGUCACCAGCACUUCCUCAGUAUCUACAGGUCACGUCACCCCUCUUCAUGUCACCAGCCCUUCCUCAUCAUCCACAGGUCAGGCCACCCCUCUUCCUGUCACCAGCACUUCCUCAUCAUCCACAGGUCAGGCCACCCCUCUUCCUGUCACCAGCACUUCCUCAGCAUCCACAGGUCACGCCACCCCUCUUCCUGUCACCGACGCUUCCUCAGUGUCCACAGGUCACGCCACGCCUCUUCCUGUCACCGACACUUCCUCAGCAUCCACAGGUGACACCACCCCUCUUCCUGUCACCGACACUUCCUCAGCAUCCACAGGUCAGGCCACCCCUCUUCCUGUCACCAGCCUUUCCUCAGUAUCCACAGGUCACGCCACCCCUCUUGCUGUCAGCAGUGCUACCUCAGCUUCCACAGUAUCCUCGGACUCCCCUCUGAAGAUGGAAACAUCAGGAAUGACAACACCGUCACUGAAGACAGACGGUGGGAGACGCACAGCCACAUCACCACCCCCCACAACCUCCCAGACCAUCAUUUCCACCAUUCCCAGCACUGCCAUGCACACCCGCUCCACAGCUGCCCCCAUCCCCAUCCUGCCUGAGAGAGGAGUUUCCCUCUUCCCCUAUGGGGCAGACGCCGGGGACCUGGAGUUCGUCAGGAGGACCGUGGACUUCACCUCCCCACUCUUCAAGCCGGCGACUGGCUUCCCCCUUGGCUCCUCUCUCCGUGAUUCCCUCUACUUCACAGACAAUGGCCAGAUCAUCUUCCCAGAGUCAGACUACCAGAUUUUCUCCUACCCCAACCCACUCCCAACAGGCUUCACAGGCCGGGACCCUGUGGCCCUGGUGGCUCCGUUCUGGGACGAUGCUGACUUCUCCACUGGUCGGGGGACCACAUUUUAUCAGGAAUACGAGACGUUCUAUGGUGAACACAGCCUGCUAGUCCAGCAGGCCGAGUCUUGGAUUAGAAAGAUCACAAACAACGGGGGCUACAAGGCCAGGUGGGCCCUAAAGGUCACGUGGGUCAAUGCCCACGCCUAUCCUGCCCAGUGGACCCUCGGGAGCAACACCUACCAAGCCAUCCUCUCCACGGACGGGAGCAGGUCCUAUGCCCUGUUUCUCUACCAGAGCGGUGGGAUGCAGUGGGACGUGGCCCAGCGCUCAGGCAAGCCGGUGCUCAUGGGCUUCUCUAGUGGAGAUGGCUAUUUCGAAAACAGCCCACUGAUGUCCCAGCCAGUGUGGGAGAGGUAUCGCCCUGAUAGAUUCCUGAAUUCCAACUCAGGCCUCCAAGGGCUGCAGUUCUACAGGCUACACCGGGAAGAAAGGCCCAACUACCGUCUCGAGUGCCUGCAGUGGCUGAAGAGCCAGCCUCGGUGGCCCAGCUGGGGCUGGAACCAGGUCUCCUGCCCUUGUUCCUGGCAGCAGGGACGACGGGACUUACGAUUCCAACCCGUCAGCAUAGGUCGCUGGGGCCUCGGCAGUAGGCAGCUGUGCAGCUUCACCUCUUGGCGAGGAGGCGUGUGCUGCAGCUACGGGCCCUGGGGAGAGUUUCGUGAAGGCUGGCACGUGCAGCGUCCUUGGCAGUUGGCCCAGGAACUGGAGCCACAGAGCUGGUGCUGCCGCUGGAAUGACAAGCCCUACCUCUGUGCCCUGUACCAGCAGAGGCGGCCCCACGUGGGCUGUGCUACAUACAGGCCCCCACAGCCCGCCUGGAUGUUCGGGGACCCCCACAUCACCACCUUGGAUGGUGUCAGUUACACCUUCAAUGGGCUGGGGGACUUCCUGCUGGUCGGGGCCCAAGACGGGAACUCCUCCUUCCUGCUUCAGGGCCGCACCGCCCAGACUGGCUCAGCCCAGGCCACCAACUUCAUCGCCUUUGCGGCUCAGUACCGCUCCAGCAGCCUGGGCCCCGUCACGGUCCAAUGGCUCCUUGAGCCUCACGACGCAAUCCGUGUCCUGCUGGAUAACCAGACUGUGACAUUUCAGCCUGACCAUGAAGACGGCGGAGGCCAGGAGACGUUCAACGCCACCGGAGUCCUCCUGAGCCGCAACGGCUCUGAGGUCUCCGCCAGCUUCGACGGCUGGGCCACCGUCUCGGUGAUCGCGCUCUCCAACAUCCUCCACUCCUCCGCCAGCCUCCCGCCCGAGUACCAGAACCGCACGGAGGGGCUCCUGGGGGUCUGGAAUAACAAUCCAGAGGACGACUUCAGGAUGCCCAAUGGCUCCACCAUUCCCCCAGGGAGCCCUGAGGAGAUGCUUUUCCACUUUGGAAUGACCUGGCAGAUCAACGGGACAGGCCUCCUUGGCAAGAGGAAUGACCAGCUGCCUUCCAACUUCACCCCUGUUUUCUACUCACAACUGCAAAAAAACAGCUCCUGGGCUGAACAUUUGAUCUCCAACUGUGACGGAGAUAGCUCAUGCAUCUAUGACACCCUGGCCCUGCGCAACGCAAGCAUCGGACUUCACACGAGGGAAGUCAGUAAAAACUACGAGCAGGCGAACGCCACCCUCAAUCAGUACCCGCCCUCCAUCAAUGGUGGUCGUGUGAUUGAAGCCUACAAGGGGCAGACCACGCUGAUUCAGUACACCAGCAAUGCUGAGGAUGCCAACUUCACGCUCAGAGACAGCUGCACCGACUUGGAGCUCUUUGAGAAUGGGACGUUGCUGUGGACACCCAAGUCGCUGGAGCCAUUCACUCUGGAGAUUCUAGCAAGAAGUGCCAAGAUUGGCUUGGCAUCUGCACUCCAGCCCAGGACUGUGGUCUGCCAUUGCAAUGCAGAGAGCCAGUGUUUGUACAAUCAGACCAGCAGGGUGGGCAACUCCUCCCUGGAGGUGGCUGGCUGCAAGUGUGACGGGGGCACCUUCGGCCGCUACUGCGAGGGCUCCGAGGAUGCCUGUGAGGAGCCGUGCUUCCCGAGUGUCCACUGCGUUCCUGGGAAGGGCUGCGAGGCCUGCCCUCCAAACCUGACUGGGGAUGGGCGGCACUGUGCGGCUCUGGGGAGCUCUUUCCUGUGUCAGAACCAGUCCUGCCCUGUGAAUUACUGCUACAAUCAAGGCCACUGCUACAUCUCCCAGACUCUGGGCUGUCAGCCCAUGUGCACCUGCCCCCCAGCCUUCACUGACAGCCGCUGCUUCCUGGCUGGGAACAACUUCAGUCCAACUGUCAACCUAGAACUUCCCUUAAGAGUCAUCCAGCUCUUGCUCAGUGAAGAGGAAAAUGCCUCCAUGGCAGAGGUCAACGCCUCGGUGGCAUACAGACUGGGGACCCUGGACAUGCGGGCCUUUCUCCGCAACAGCCAAGUGGAACGAAUCGAUUCUGCAGCACCGGCCUCGGGAAGCCCCAUCCAACACUGGAUGGUCAUCUCGGAGUUCCAGUACCGCCCUCGGGGCCCGGUCAUUGACUUCCUGAACAACCAGCUGCUGGCCGCGGUGGUGGAGGCGUUCUUAUACCACGUUCCACGGAGGAGUGAGGAGCCCAGGAACGACGUGGUCUUCCAGCCCAUCUCCGGGGAAGACGUGCGCGAUGUGACAGCCCUGAACGUGAGCACGCUGAAGGCUUACUUCAGAUGCGAUGGCUACAAGGGCUACGACCUGGUCUACAGCCCCCAGAGCGGCUUCACCUGCGUGUCCCCGUGCAGUAGGGGCUACUGUGACCAUGGAGGCCAGUGCCAGCACCUGCCCAGUGGGCCCCGCUGCAGCUGUGUGUCCUUCUCCAUCUACACGGCCUGGGGCGAGCACUGUGAGCACCUGAGCAUGAAACUCGACGCGUUCUUCGGCAUCUUCUUUGGGGCCCUGGGCGGCCUCUUGCUGCUGGGGGUCGGGACGUUCGUGGUCCUGCGCUUCUGGGGUUGCUCCGGGGCCAGGUUCUCCUAUUUCCUGAACUCAGCUGAGGCCUUGCCUUGAAGGGGCAGCUGUGGCCUAGGCUACCUCAAGACUCACCUCAUCCUUACCGCACAUUUAAGGCGCCAUUGCUUUUGGGAGACUGGAAAAGGGAAGGUGACUGAAGGCUGUCAGGAUUCUUCAAGGAGAAUGAAUACUGGGAAUCAAGACAAGACUAUACCUUAUCCAUAGGCGCAGGUGCACAGGGGGAGGCCAUAAAGAUCAAACAUGCAUGGAUGGGUCCUCACGCAGACACACCCACAGAAGGACACUAGCCUGUGCACGCGCGCGUGCACACACACACACACACAAGAGUUCAUAAUGUGGUGAUGGCCCUAAGUUAAGCAAAAUGCUUCUGCACACAAAACUCUCUGGUUUACUUCAAAUUAACUCUAUUUAAAUAAAGUCUCUCUGACUUUUUGUGUCU